GCUUCUGUUCCCUGGAAGCAGAGUGGCUGCAGCUGUGAGCUCCAGGGACUCACCAGCCAAAGCUCCAGCCAAAGCUCCAACUCUGUGGCCAGGCUGGUCCAGGCCUCUGUGGGCCAGGCUACUUCCAAAGACCCACUUCUCCCACAGUAAAUAUAUGGCCAUCCCGGGGCUUUCCUUUCUGGAGGAGAGAACAUAAUGGAGCAUCCUCUAGGACAGGAAAAUAUUUUAAGGAAUAAUCCAGUAUCAUUAUUGCCAUCUGCAGAAUGCCUUUCCUACACCAUUCCUACACUAAAGGAAUUACAGCUUCACUGGGAGGAAGGAGAUAUAGACAAAAGAAGCAAAACAAAACAAAAACAAAAAAAAACAAGCAGACAAGCCUGGGUAUAGUGGCUCACGCCUGUAAUGCCAGCACUUUGGGAGGCCAAGGUGGCUGGGUCGCUUGACCCCAGGAGUUCGAGACCAGUCUGGGCAACAUCAGGAGACCCUGUCUCUACAAAAAAUACAAAAUUAGUGGGACAUGGUGGCGCACACCUGUAGUCCCAGCUACUCGGGGGGUGGCUGAGGCAGAAAGACGGCUUGAGCCCAGGACAUCAAGCCUACAGUGAGAUAUGAUCGUGCCACUGAACUUCAGCCUGGACUAUAGAGUGGGACCCUCUCUCAGUUUAAGAAAAAAAAUAAAAUAAAACAAGCAGACAAACAUACAUUGCAAUGUAGGAUGGCUUCCUCCGGGAGGCCUAGCCAGGAGUGGGUUCAGCAGCCCCGGGCCGGCAUUGCCGCUGCCCUGUCUCCUCGCUCUGUGAUGCUGGUCCAGAGCCUCACCAAGCCUCAGUGUCCUCAUCUUUAAAGUGGGUCUCACCGGCCGGGCUUGGUAACUCAUGCCUGUAAUCCCAGCUCUUUGGGAGGCCGAGGAGGGUGGAUCACUUGAGGUCAGGAGUUGAAGACCAGCCUGGCCAACAUGGUGAAACUCCAUCUUUACUAAAUAUACAAAAAUUAGCCAGGUGUGGUGGUGUGUGCCUGUAAUCCCAGCUACUCAGGAGGCUGAGGCAGGAGAAUCACUUGAACCCAGGAGGCAGGGGCUGCAGUGAGCCAAGAUCCCGCUACUGCACUCCAGCCUGGGUUACAGAGCGAGACUCCAUCUCAAAAAAUAAAUAAACAAAUAAAAAUUUAAAAAUAAUAAAGUGGGUCUUGCCUUACCUACUAGGAUAGUUGUUAGAUGUGGGAGAGAUGCCAUAAGCAGUGCCCAGGGCACUCCACAGCCCGAGAAAUCUAAGCUCAUCUCUCCUUCCCCUUGCUGGAGGACAACAACGUUCAAGAGAACAACAGGAAGCUUUCCCAUGAGUGGAAGGAUGUUGUGUCAGCUUCUCACUGACCCCACUUCACGGAUCUGUCUGCUCAAACCAACCUCCCCAACCCCCAGCUUUUAAAUGUGCCUCUUUCACAGUUUCCAACUUGUUGCUCAAUAUUACAGUAGCCAUCAGCGUCGCAGUGUUGGCCUAAUGGAAGUCUUCACUUGGUAAAGGUUUACUUUAGAGAACAUUAUGAUUGGUUUUUGCUCUAAUUCUUUAAGAAACUGAUAGUUGUGGUUUCCUACUAUCAUGUGUGAGCCACAAACCAAUAAAAUACCUGAUCUAUUUGUAGUACAAAAAUUAGCGGAAUGUGGUAGUGCACACCUGUAGUCCCAGCUACUUGGGAGGCUGAGGCAAGAGGACUGCUUGAGCCCAGGAGGUUGAGGCUGCAGUGAGCCAUGAUUGCACCGCUGCACAAUAAGGCAAGAGUUCAGUGUAUUCUUGCCUUAUUUUUUAAAAAUCAGCUGCAAGUUUAAUUUCAAGUUAUGAUUUGUGUUUGAUUGGGGUUGUCAAUCGUGCAACCAUUGGCAAAGUGCCAACAGGUUCUACCAAAAUUGGUCUUUUCCCAUGUGGUUUUAGUCUGGUUUGACUCAAGCCUGCUGCCACUGUCUGCAGCCCUGCUCCAGAAACUUCUGCAUGGCAUUGGGUUUUAUUUUACAUUAAAAUAAAUCAGCAUUGCAUUGGAAGAUUGAUCAUUUCUAUCAAUCCUCUUGAGAUAUUGGAGGUAUAACUUCCAUUCCUGGCUUCUUCCCUUGCUUGGCCCCAGUCAAACAUCACGAGUCACUCUUUUUAGCAUCUUUUCUGGUUCAUUUUGGGGAGUGGAAAGGAUGGACUCUUGUAAUAAGUUAUUCCUACAAAAAAGCAGUUCCCCUAUCUGCAGUGAUCCUCAAGUAAUCAUUUCUUGCCCAAAAACCAAUGCCCUCUCAGUCCCCUGCCAUCAUGCUCUAUGUAAUACUGGGUUCCACUGCACCCUGGAAACCCUCUGUGCUUUAAUAUGUUACUCAACAGAUUUUCCCCGGUUGUUUUAUAUAGCUGCCCCAGUAGGUGCUUUGGCAUUAUAUAGACUAUCUUUUAAAUUUUAUUUAUAAUUGUUGUUUCCAUAUACAAAUCCUUUUUUUUUUUUUUGUAUUAGUAACUUUAUACCUUGUGACCUUAACUCAUAUAUUGCCUCUAGUGGCUAUUUUUGAAUCCUUUGGGAUUUUCUACAUAGACUAUUAUGUCAUUUGAGAAUAAAGUUUUAUUUUUUUCUUUUCAAUGCUUAUGUCUUUUAAUUCUUUUUCCUAACUUAUUGCAUUGGCUAUGAUUUCCAGGAUAAUGUUAAAUAGGAGUGGGACAAAUCCUUGCUUUGUUCCCAGUGCUGGGGAGAGGUAUUAAGUCUUUCACCAUUAAGAAUAAUUUGAGCUGUAGAUUUGCCCAAAUAGACUUAAAAUUCCUUAGUUACCAGAAGUAUUUUUUCUGCUUCUUGGGCUUCAAACACACCUCAUGGGUCAGCUUUUAAAUGUAUAACAAUAUACAUUUAAACAAUUUUUUAAAAAUAUAACAAUUUAUAACAACUUUUAAUUGUGUGCUGUAGAGUCUUUAUUUGAUAUGAUUUAAAAUAUCUAGUUUUGUCAGGACUAAGAUAGCAAGUAGUCUAUUUUAGUGGAAAACAUCAUGUACUGCAUUCACUAUUUAAAAAUAGUAACAAUCAAAACAUGCUUCCACCCUUCACCAGUGCAGACGUGCAGUGACGACUGAGCAAGGUCUCAUUCACAGGUAGAUAGCAGCCUAAUCAAUAAUCCCAGUGUGAGGCUGCCAUGCUGACCACUCAGAACAAAACAAGCGAGCUAAAUUCAUCCACUGAAGAAUGGGUCAACAAAAUGUGGUAUAUCCAUGCAAUGGAAUAUUAUUCAGCCAUUAAAAGGAAUGAAGUACUGGUACAUGCUACAAUAGGGAUAAAUCUCAAAAAAUAAUACUAUUAUAAGUGAAAGAACCCAGUCACAGAAGGCCACGUAUAGUGUGAGUCCAUUUAUAUGAAAUACUCAGAAUAGGCCAAUCCAUAAAGACAGAAAGUAGAUUGGUGUUGCCAGGGGCUGGGGACAGGAUGGAGCUUGGGAGCUAGUGAGCUAAUAGUGGGUGUGGGGUUUCUUUUUGAAUGAUGAAAAUGUUCUAAUAUUAGAUUACAUUGAUGGUUUCAAGCUGGGUGAAUAUACUAAAAACCAUUGAACUGCACACUUUAAACAAGUGAACUUUAUCGUAUGAAAAUUAUGUCUCAAUAAAACUGUUUUUUUUUAAAAAAUAAAAUAACAUGAGAGCUAAUUUAAUGGGAGGCUGGGCAUGGAGGCUCAUGCCUGUAAUCCCAGCACUUUGUGAGCCCGAGGCGAGCAGAUCACUUGAGGCCAGGAGUUCGAGACUAGCCUGGCCAACAUGGUGAAACCCUGUCUCUACUAAAAAUAUAAAAAUUAGCAGGGCGUGGUGGCACAUACCUGUAGUCCUGGCUACUCAGGAGGCUGAGGCAGGAGAAUCGCUUGAACUGGGAGGCGAAGUUUGCAGUGAGCUGAGAUCACUCCAUUGCACUCCAGCCUGGGCGACAGAGCAAGACUCACUCCGUCUCAAAAAAAAAAAAAAUUAAUUAAUUAAUGGAAUUGAUCAGGCUAGAUAAAGAUUAAGCUAGAAAGCUGGAGAAAGUGAGCUGCCCCAGACCAGGUUGUAAAAGGCUCUUCUGGGGGGAGGAUGGGCUAAAGGAACUACUUGAAGGGGAGGGAACCCUAUAGGCCACAGCAGAGGCAGCUGACUGAUGGAGCAUCUUGGGGGCUAGGUCAGUGGCCACACCCCACCAUCAACUGAUCAUUAGAGGUUGUAUUAAAGUGUGGGGUAGGACAUGGUUAAAAGCUGAUGAUUGCAGCCAAAAGAAGUAUCAUCUAGAUAAAGAGGUCUCCAGAAGACCCUGAACAAUUAAGCAAAAAUGGGAUAGUCGACUAGUGCUGUACAGAAGGAAAUGGCUAGAAUUAGCAGCCAACUCCUGUUAACCAGAAAACUGACUUUUUUUUUCUUCUUUCUUCUUCAGACUAUAGCCUUCACUUUCCCUCGGUCCACCAUGGAGCCCUUGUGUCCACUCCUGCUGGUGGGUUUUAGCUUGCCGCUCGCCAGGGCUCUCAGGGGCAACGAGACCACUGCCGACAGCAACGAGACAACCACGACCUCAGGCCCUCCGGACCCGGGCGCCUCCCAGCCGCUGCUGGCCUGGCUGCUACUGCCGCUGCUGCUCCUCCUCCUCGUGCUCCUUCUCGCCGCCUACUUCUUCAGGUUCAGGAAGCAGAGGAAAGCUGUGGUCAGCACCAGCGACAAGAAGAUGCCCAACGGAAUCUUGGAGGAGCAAGAGCAGCAAAGGGUGAUGCUGCUCAGCAGGUCACCCUCAGGGCCCAAGAAGUAUUUUCCCAUCCCCGUGGAGCACCUGGAGGAGGAGAUCCGUAUCAGAUCCGCCGACGACUGCAAGCAGUUUCGGGAGGAGUUCAACUCAUUGCCAUCUGGACACAUACAAGGAACUUUUGAACUGGCAAAUAAAGAAGAAAACAGAGAAAAAAACAGAUAUCCCAACAUCCUUCCCAAUGACCAUUCUAGGGUGAUUCUGAGCCAACUGGAUGGAAUUCCCUGUUCAGACUACAUCAAUGCUUCCUACAUAGAUGGUUACAAAGAGAAGAAUAAAUUCAUAGCAGCUCAAGGUCCCAAACAGGAAACGGUUAACGACUUCUGGAGAAUGGUCUGGGAGCAAAAGUCUGCGACCAUCGUCAUGUUAACAAACUUGAAAGAAAGGAAAGAGGAAAAGUGCCAUCAGUACUGGCCCGACCAAGGCUGCUGGACCUAUGGAAACAUCCGGGUGUGCGUGGAGGACUGCGUGGUUUUGGUCGACUACACCAUCCGGAAGUUCUGCAUACAGCCACAGCUCCCCGACGGCUGCAAAGCCCCCAGGCUGGUCUCACAGCUGCACUUCACCAGCUGGCCCGACUUCGGAGUGCCUUUUACCCCCAUUGGGAUGCUGAAGUUCCUCAAGAAAGUAAAGACGCUCAACCCCGUGCACGCUGGGCCCAUCGUGGUCCACUGUAGCGCGGGCGUGGGCCGGACGGGCACCUUCAUUGUGAUCGAUGCCAUGAUGGCCAUGAUGCACGCGGAGCAGAAGGUGGAUGUGUUUGAAUUUGUGUCUCGAAUCCGUAAUCAGCGCCCUCAGAUGGUUCAAACGGAUAUGCAGUACACGUUCAUCUACCAAGCCUUACUCGAGUACUACCUCUACGGGGACACAGAGCUGGACGUGUCCUCCCUGGAGAAGCACCUGCAGACCAUGCACGGCACCACCACCCACUUCGACAAGAUCGGGCUGGAGGAGGAGUUCAGGAAAUUGACAAAUGUCCGGAUCAUGAAGGAGAACAUGAGGACGGGCAACUUGCCGGCAAACAUGAAGAAGGCCAGGGUCAUCCAGAUCAUCCCGUAUGACUUCAACCGAGUGAUCCUUUCCAUGAAAAGGGGUCAAGAAUACACAGACUACAUCAACGCAUCCUUCAUAGACGGCUACCGACAGAAGGACUAUUUCAUCGCCACCCAGGGGCCACUGGCACACACGGUUGAGGACUUCUGGAGGAUGAUCUGGGAAUGGAAAUCCCACACUAUCGUGAUGCUGACGGAGGUGCAGGAGAGAGAGCAGGAUAAAUGCUACCAGUAUUGGCCAACCGAGGGCUCAGUUACUCAUGGAGAAAUAACGAUUGAGAUAAAGAAUGAUACCCUUUCAGAAGCCAUCAGUAUACGAGACUUUCUGGUCACUCUCAAUCAGCCCCAGGCCCGCCAGGAGGAGCAGGUCCGAGUAGUGCGCCAGUUUCACUUCCACGGCUGGCCUGAGAUCGGGAUUCCCGCCGAGGGCAAAGGCAUGAUUGACCUCAUCGCAGCCGUGCAGAAGCAGCAGCAGCAGACAGGCAACCACCCCAUCACCGUGCACUGCAGUGCCGGAGCUGGGCGAACAGGUACAUUCAUAGCCCUCAGCAACAUUUUGGAGCGAGUAAAAGCCGAGGGACUUUUAGAUGUAUUUCAAGCUGUGAAGAGUUUACGACUUCAGAGACCACAUAUGGUGCAAACCCUGGAACAGUAUGAAUUCUGCUACAAAGUGGUACAAGAUUUUAUUGAUAUAUUUUCUGAUUAUGCUAAUUUCAAAUGAAGAUUCCUGCCUUAAAAUAUUUUUUAAUUUAAUGGUCAGUAUAUUUUGUAAAAAUCAUGUUAAUUUAUUUCAUAGUUGACAUUAAUAUCUUCCCUAAUUUCUUUGUAUAUAUUUUGUUAUGCCUUAAAGGCCACCUGCUAUACAGUUGUUAAAUCUUAAAUAUGCUUUUUAAAAAUUGGAAUAAUGUAUUAAGGUCAAAUAAUAUCCCAUAAAAUAUAUAUUUCUGCUAAUAUUAGUAAAUAUCUUAAUUUUUCAUUAGAUUCAUAUCAUUUAAUUUCACAUAUUCAACACCUUUAAAUGUUGUAAUCUUAAUAUGCGAAGUGUGCCUCUGCAAGAUACUAACACAAAGCUCAUGUUAAGAAAACAGUUGAGGACUCAGAAGUCAGUUCGAAAAUGCACUUUCCUAACAGUGAAUUCACAACCCUGAACAGCAGCAUUUUUGGAAGGCAAACUGUUCGUGAUGGUACAAUGUAAAUGGGGACUUCUGUAAAGUUCUCAGUUUCGGUCCAUGUGGUUUAUCUUUACAUUUUAAAGAUCAAAGAAGUCUUUACAACCUGAAUCCAGGUCUAAAACACACUAGAGUAGCUGGUGACUAUAAAUAAUAUUUUAAAAUGCUGUGUCUACACCAUCAAGACUGUGUCUACACUAUCUUGGCUGAACGAGAAGAGAUGUAAAUGCUGGGUGGUCCCGUUGACCCACGGCGUUGGGUACAACAAAACCAGCCAUCGGAGUUACACCCCAAAGCACCAUUUGCUGUCCAGCUGCCUGUCGUUUGGCCCAGACCACCCUCAGAAAAAAACCAGCUGCCUCUCCCAUUCUCCCCUCCCGUUCUGCCACAGCGGCCUGGGCUGGUCCAGUGCUAUGCCUGGAGGCUCAACACAAAACUUCCCAUCCAAACAUUCAGAUGAACUGAGCGUCUUACACACGCAGUACAGAGGAGCACACAUUAGGAUAGAAACAGUAGAAUAACCACGGGCAAUUAAACUUUAAAUUUUCUGAGCAGCAUUUUGGUAUUUAAACAUUUCUUGUAAAAAGCUGAGACAGUUUGUAAGAAAAGAAUCCUUAAAAUCUAGAUUUAUACCAUUUUUUAAAGUCCCACCUUUCAAUGUUUAAUAAAACAAAAAGAGAAAUCCUUAAUCUAAAAGCUAAAUUAUUUUUGAAUGGAAAUACUACUGAGACCAUUGACACUGGAUAACAGUAAUGAUCCCAUUACCAGAUAAGAUUGACUGACGGGGAAAAAAAAAAAAAAAGAAUGGGGUGUGAAUGUACCAACACUGAAUCUUACAGCAGUUAUCUUUCUAUGGCCAUUAGGUACCUAGCAGAUGUGCACAAUAUAAACAAAAAGAUAUCUGGCCUACCUUACUACUAAAAGCAUUUAACACGUGCAUUUUUGGUACUUUUUUUUUUGUUUUCUAAAAGCUACAUAAAGGCCUUAUUUGACAUUUUCACUGAUAACUGAUCGCACCCUCAUGUUGCAGUGUUCGUCCCCUAUUCAUUAACAGUGUGUGCAAAUGCAACCCCAGGACACAUUAUUGUUCUGAUAGAUGCUCACAGGGAAUCAAGCUUCUCGCCCACUCCACGGCUCUGAGCCCCAUCCAAGGGCAAGACUUGGUGCCCAGCUGGAAGGACGAAAGCACACUUUGUGACCGCCAUCCUCACCAGCUGCAUGCCUGGGCUGCACACUGCUGAACGUGCUCCUCUCUCCUUCUCUGUACAAUGAUUCAGCAUCUCGGCGGAAGAGGAAAAUGGAGCUUUUUGAGGCUCGCCAGGUCCCUUUUGUUUUCACCAUUAAAAUUCCAAACCCAAAGCCUUUGUUUGACUGAAGGAGAAGAGAGGGAAGUAAGCUUCUGUUCAGCACCUGAACCCUAGAAAAAGAGCCAGUUUGCUACGAUGAAGGUGACAUUUCUCUGGUCAUUUAUUUGAGAGUUCGAAGUCAAAGUCGAGGGGCACCGGCUUUGGUUCAUGUCUAGGAGCCCUCUGUCAGAAUCCUUGAAGCCCUUUAAUGGUCUAACUGGCAUCUCUUGUAUCAAGAAGUACCUUUAAGGUAGACCUUUUCAGGGUGCCCUCAGGAAAGGGCCCUGCUCAUGUUUUUUUCCUGUCCCCUUAGACCAACCCCAGGUGUCCACUGCAGGGGUUCUGCCUGUUCCCAAACUUUUUCCAUUCCAGGAACAAAGGAGAAGCCACUUUCCCCAGGACGCAAGACUCUCCCCUCCACUGUCCGGGACAGCGUUCGCCCUUUAGCGGGGAGGUCAUUACAGCCUCAUGGCCUCUACCAAGGCCCCAGAUCACAGGAUCUCCUGGGCCUUGGAGCACCUCACGCUGGGGGAAUCAAUCCCUGAGGGACUCAGAAUCUUCUCCGUGCAACCUGGAAAGUUCAUCUCUUGUUUCCUUCAGUCAAAGAAAGUCCAUUGUACAUAACAAAACAGCCCCCAAACAGCCCAGUGCCGACACCAUUGUUCCUUUCACACUUUCCUUUGUUGCAUGCAGUUGGGUUCAAAUGCCAAAUAGUGAUUAGAAGACGACCAUUCUGAUCUGUGUGUGAUCUGGUCACUAUGUGACUGCCUUUACGGUUUCUCUCCAUGUGCUAUAUGAAUGAAGAAUGCAUACCAGUGUUUUAAAAGGUAUUUUUAUGUGUUUUUAAACACUUUUUUAAAUGAGCCUGACACCUGUGUUUCAGCAUUUGGAGACAUCCCCAUGUUAUUCUUUUAAGUGUAUAAUUACUGAUACUUUUUUGUUUGUUUGUUUAACUAAGUUGUGUUUAACUUAUGUGCAGUCUUUAUAAUGUAUGUAUGUUAUUACAGUUUCAACUAUCAUAUUUUCUUUGAUUACAUUUAUAAUUUGAUCUUGCUCUGAUUAUAAUGCCAGUGAAUGUUGCUGAACUCUUUGUAUAUGCAAAUUGCAAGAUUUAAACCAUUCUGAUGCAAGGAUAAACCUUUACUUUGACUACCA